CUGAGCCACCACGCCUGGCCACAUUUUUUAUUCUUAUGUGAGCUUGAUGGGCUGAAUGCUAAGUAUUUUAUUUCAGGAUAACCAAUUAUUGCAUAUUAGUAUAAAUGAGCUGUUGGGGACAGGAUACUUAGAAGUGCAACCCUUAGAGCAUAUUCCCCCUCAAAUUUUUGGAUGUAGUUUGAAAAAUAAAAGCCAGCCUUUUAGCUUUGAAAACCCAGCGUCUGUGUGCCUCAAUCUCUUCCUCUGAAAAGUGGGGCAUUUGGACUGCGAUACUUAAUUAGUGCUGAAUGUAGUUCUGUGAAAAUAAUUGGCAAAUGUAUUGCCGAUGGUCCCCAUUAUUUCUUACAUCAUAUCAAAAAGAUUACAUUGUAAUGUUAGAUUUCCUGUAUUCUAAUUAGUUGCCUAAUGUAGUGUCAUAAGUAUCUAUAGUCUUAGCAAAAGCCAUAUUUUUCUGUCCAGGUGCAGUGGCUUACAUCCGUAGCCCCAACACUUUGGGAUGCCAAAGCAGGAAGAUCACUUGAGCCCAGGGGUUUGAGAGCAGCCUGGGAAACAUAGGGAAACCCCAUCUGUGGAAAAAAAAAAUAAUUAGCUGGGCGUGGUAGCACAUGUCUGUGGUUCGAGCUACUCUGGAGGCUGAAGAGGGAGGAUUGUCUGGGCAUGGGAGUUUGAGGCGACAGUGAGCCAUGAUCACACCAUUGCACUCCAACCUGGGCAACAGAACAAGACCCUGCCUCAAAAAAAAAAAAAAUCCUGUAUUUUUCUGACCUAGAAUUAGAAUCCAUGAUCUGUUAUUCUAAAUGGUCUGUGAAUACAAAAUAAUUUAAAAUAGUACUGACCUACCUAGAACAUCAGUAUAUUGGAAGGUUUCAGCUGUGAGUGACAGAAAACCUGAAACAAGUGGCUUAAAAUAAGAUUAAAAUGUAUUUCUUUUUUUUUUUUUUUUUUUUUUGAGAUGGAGUCUUGCUCUGUCGGUUGCCCAGGCUGGAGUGCAGUGGCGCGAUCUCGGCUCACUGCAACCUCUGCCACCUGGGUUCAAGCAACUCUCCUGCCUCAGCCUCCCGAGUAGCUGGGACUACAGGCACCCACCACCACGCCUGGCUAAUUUUUGUAUUUUUUUUUUUAGUAGAGAAUGGGGUUUCACCGUGUUAGCCAGGAUGGUCUCGAUCCCCUGACCUCGUGAUCCGCCUGCCUCGGCCUCUCAAAGUGCUGGGAUUACAGGCGUGAGCCACCACGCCCAGCCUAAAAUGUAUUUCUUAUUCAUGUAAAAGUUGGUACAGAUCUGGAAUGGAGCUUCAUGGCAUCAGGGACAUUUUACCACUUACUCCUAGUUCUCUCUUACCACUCUGCCCUCCUCUUGGGUGUAAACCUCAUUUUUAUUGAGGAAAAUGGUAGCACCUAUUGCAGGUACAGGAUGGAGAAAGGGAUGAAGCAGAAGAUAGAAGGCACCUGUCAGUAUUCUGUUAAGCAUGAUUCCCAGACAACUUCAUGUGCAUCAGUUACAUUGGCCAGAACUGAGACAUAUGGCCGUGCACAGCUGCAAGGAAGGCUAGGAAGUGUAGUCACAUGCCCAACCAAAAAUUCUAAUUAAGUGGAAGAAAGGGAGAACAGAUAUUGAGGGUGGGGUAGGACAGAAAACCAUCAGUCUCUGAUACAGACUCAUUAAUGAUAAACAAAAGGAAAACCAAAGAGCAGCUACCAUUCUCUAGCUUCCUCUAGAGAAGGAGGCUUCUGUUUCUCGUAGCCGAUACUGAUUCUCUAAAUGGAAAUGUCCAUUCGGAGAAUAUACUAAUAUACAAGAUCCGAUCUCUACAAAAUAUAUAUAUUUUAAAAAGAAUAUGUCAUUCUCUUUUCUGUAAUUGUGUUAGUGCAGAGAAUCUUCCAAAAGAAACCUGCUAAAUAUAUUUUCUGGUUUGAAUUUUGGAGUUGAUAUUAUGGUUUAUGAGCCAACCUCUUGUGAGUUUGGUUAAGUGUAAAUUUUUCCAGUGAGUCUGUGAGCCCCUGGGGAAAAUGAUGAAGUAGAGAAUAGACCCAACUCUUGACGUACUGUGACCUUACUGGGAGCAUAUAUCUUGUACAGCUUCAUAUGACCUGAGGCACUCAUCAUUCAUUCCUGAUCUUGAAGGAAGAGAAAAAUUACAAACUUGUAUAGUCUUCAAUAUAUCCAUCUAUAAAACCAGAAUAAUAGCGCUUUGUGUGAUGAAGAUUAGUAGUAGUCUUGUAAAACAUUUUUAUAAAGGAAAGAGAGCUUUCAGGGCUAAUGAAAUUGCAAGUCUUGAUUCUUUAAGACUCAUUUAGAGGAUUAUUCACUGUUCUGAAAUGAUUGUGAUUUUUCAGCAUUUUUGAAAAAAAAAAGCAGAACCAAAUUCACCCCCCAAAUAUUGAAAUAACAUUUGAUCUGCCCCAUCGUCUCAGUUGUUCCAUUGGCUGCCUAAAAUCAUUUUAAAGAUGAAGUCUUCACAUAUCUUUCUUAAAAGAACGAGGUGAUCCUAGUAAACAAAGGGGAGACUUCCAGGCAGUGCUUAGGACUGUAAUUUUUAGAAAUGCAAGGUAAUUAUCACCAGUGUCAAACUACCAGGCAGCCUGCACACUUUGCUGAUUCAUAACCAUUUGAAGAAUGCUGAAUUAGUCAUGAACAUCUUAGAUGCUGUUUUGUGGCUGUAGAAUUUUCCUUCUACAAAAUUUAGAUCUAAAAACAGAUAGGGUUUUAAUUUAUACAGGUUGGCUAUCUGGAAAUUGUUGUUGAAGAAAUGUGGCUAAACUAAUGUCUGUUUCUCAGUAUUCUGUACCCUGCCCCUGUCACUUCAGAAAGGAGUCCACUUGUGGUUCAGGCUCAAAGAUGUAGAUCUAACCCAGAGUGGCCCAGGGAGAUGUGGCUCAGGCCCAAAUGAUUCCUAACCCCAAUGCCAGCCUCACACCAGAGAACAAAAAGAGACCUGAUGGGAAUGAUGAGCACUCACUAUAUGCCAGGCACACCCCAGAGGUGGAUGUGGGUAACUCUCCCUAUAUUAUAGAUGGGACAUUGAGACUUGCCUACAAGUCCCCGUGGUGGGGCGUGGCUAAACUCAACUCUGUAAGGUUACUGCCUCUGCUAUGCCAUCUUUCAUGGAACCCACUUAGUGCCAUGCAGCUUUCUCUAAUUUGCUCUCAGUUCCUGGCUAUGAAUUGCUAAACUAUCAGUGACAUUGUUUUCUCUCACUUUUAAGGCUGUACAAUGAAAGAAUCUUCCAUUUUUCAUUUGUUAGCUUGUUGCUGUUUUACCACUCUAGAAGUGCUUGUGGUUUACUAAACUUCUUUAUUUCACUUUUAGUACGUGCAGUUUAUGCAUUCUAGUCUUUUGUCUUCAGGGAUUCUAAACUCCUGUAGGAAUUCUAAUACCUUUUUGGGUAACUAAGAAUUCACCAUUAAAGUCCUGGAAUUAAUGUGUUCAAUCUAGAAUCCUCAAGAAUAAGAAGUGAGCUGUCGAGGUUUAUAGAGAACCCUGUUGACACUUCUCCCAGAGUAGCUUCAACAGGGUCCAAAGACUCGUCACCUUUCCCAGGGGUUUGGUUUUGAAUUAGGAUCACUGACAGUUCAGCAACUUUAUGCUACCAAUUAGAAAAGGAGAUCACUAUGUAGAGAAAAUUUAGUGCCUUCUAAUCACCUUUGUAUACUUGAAUUUAGUUAUUAAUUUACCCUGUCUGUAGAAUGAACAAACUCAACUCCUUUAAUUUAAAACAAAUGAAAUAACUCUUUAAUGACUGCUCCAUUAAACAGAGUUGUAUUGAUUUCUAUCUGUUAUACUCCAGAGGUAGGUGUUUUAACCCUGUGCUUUUCCGGGGAGUUAUAACUGACUGUUGAUGGACAGGUGUCACAAAUACAACUGAUACAUUCAGAUUGUCACAGCCAAUUCCUACCUUUAUUUAAAGAGUGAUUUUCUUUUUUCUAUCUUUAGGGCCACUCUGGCUCUUUAUUUCAGGAUGUUUUCUUGAUUAUCUCAUAGACCUAGCAAUUCCCAAAGGAGGUUUGUAAUAUUCAAUACUGUUUCGAGAAGUGCCAUGACAUUUUCAGAAUAAAAUGAACAUUGAUUAAUUUUAAUUUAAAAGACACAGUUCUUUGUCACAGAUUGGAGGAGACUAAAGAGAUACAAUUAAUGCAAUGUGGGAUCCUAGAACAGAAAAAGAAUAUUAGUGGGAAAGCUGGUGAAAAUUGCAUAAAGUCUGUAUUUUAGUUAAUAGGAUUAUAUCUGUUGAUUUCCUGUCUUUCUGCUAUCCUUAGGUAAGAUUUUAACAUUUGGGGAAGUUAGGCGAAGGGUAUUUGGGAACUCUUGCAACUUUUCUAUAAAUCGAAAAUUAUUUCAAAAUAAAAAGUUUAAAAAUAUAUACCUUGUUGCCAGUUAUUUAGAAAUUAUGGUGUGGGCCUUUCUGGAGGCCCUCUAAGGCAGUGAAGAUGAUCCAAGAUGCAUCAGCAUACUAACUGCCCACAGGAACCAACCACGGAAAUUGUUUUUACUUGUGUAUCCAUUCUAACCCUACCAGUGCAGUCCAGGCUUAUCAAGGUCCAUGGAAGGCAGCAGGUUCUCAUGGGAAGAGUAAGAGGUUUGAUUUCAGAUAUGUGGCCAGGAGUGGUGGCUCACGCCUGUAAUCCCAGCACUUUGGGAGGCUGAAGUGGGCAGAUCACUUGAGGUCAGGAGUUUGAGACCAGCCUGGCCAACAUGGUGAAACCCUGUCUCUACUAAAAAUACAAAACUUAGCUGGGUGUGGUGACGGGCUCCUGUAAUCCAGCUACUCGGGAGGCUGAGGCAGGAAAAUCACUUGAAUGUGGGAGGUGGAGGUUGCAGUGAGCUGAGAUCGGGCCACUGUACUCCAGCCUGGGUAGUAGAGUGAGACUCUGCCUCAAAAAAAAAAAGAUGUGAGUUUUCAGUUUCUUCUACCACUCACUAGUGGUUUCAGUUUGGGCAGCUAGCCUGACUUUUCUGAGUCUCAGUUUUUCAUCUGAAUACUGGGGAGCAUAAUAUCUAUCCCAUAGUGAUUAUAAGGAUUAAAUAAUAUGUAUACAACCUAGUCACAAACUCUAAAGCACAAUGUAAAAUGUUCAUUUUGAUUAAUAUCCAAAUUAAUCACUUGGAAAAAAAAGGUUCUCCAGUUUCAGGGAUUAUACAUCAGGCUAACUCUUUUUAGGUAAUUUUUCCUAGAUUAAUUGUAUUGCUACAUUGGAUGUAAUCAAAAUCCAUAGAUGAUAUAUUUAAAAUUGUGCUUAUAACAUUUUUAUUAUUAACAAUCCAUUUGAACCUAAACCAAUAUGACAAAGAAACAAAGUAGUAAGCUGAACACUGUAGUCUAUUUAAUACAAAGAUUUACUUGCAUAUUAUUUUGACUUAUUUAAGCCAAUGUCUAGCCUUUUUGCUUUGGAAAUUAUGACACUAGGAAGAGAAUUUCAAAUAUGAAAAUCCCAAAUCUGUCAGUUUCCAUGAAAUUUAAAGCCAAAGUCAUUAAUGGAAUCCAUGGAGCUAUUUUCAAGGGAGACCCUAGAGAGAUACAAUGUCCAGUCUACCAAUUGUACGAGACUUACAACCUUGUAGUUUGUUUGCAGAAGUAAAUUAUUCUAUAACUAAUUGAAAACAAGGAGCUUAUUCAAAAUACUGAAGUGUACAAAUGAACAACAGCAAAAAAAAAAAAGACAAAAUACUGAAGUGCUACCAGGUACCUGUGAUGAAAUUUUAUAUUUCUUGUUUUACAUCCAAGUUUGUAAUCUGUGUUACAAACUUACAUCUAAAGUUUAUUCUAAGUCCGUAUUUCAUGUGGCUUCAUGCUCUGAUUCUGCCUGGUAAAGUGCUGCAGUGUGGUUUCAACCAGAUUGUAAUUAUUAUUCUUCCUGUAUGUUGAUAUAACUGCUUUACUAAAGUAGCCUCACAUAGCUCAAUCAGAGUUUUCUCCAAAAAUGUCAGUCUAAUGCCAAAACCAAAAGAGAUCAAAGACAUGGAAGAUUUCCUAGUGAAGUCAGAGCUGCUCAUCAGUAGUGCUUACCUUUGAAUAAAGAGAAAUACUUUAAAAAGCCAACUGUUAUUGAGUGGGUAAAGUAAUGAGUAAGAUCUCUGUUAUCCUCAAGGAGUAUUGUAUUGCUACACUGGAUGUAAUCAAUGUAGUAUUAGAGGAUUACAAUCAAUGUAAUUCUGCGCUCAAGGAGUACAUUUUCCAACUCAGUAAAAAGUAGUGUAUUAGCAAGUAUAGAUGGAAAUUCCGUGUGUGUGUGUGUGUGUGUGCGUGUGUGUGUGUAUAUAGCCACACAUAUUCUAUUCAUGAAACGGCAAUCUCAUUAGAUUAAGACAAUAAUGUGCAUUAUUCAUGUUAUUUUACUGUCAUUCGAGAGAUAUUAGACAACUGAGAAGAAACAAUUUAUAUAUAAUUAUAAAUGUAUAAUUAAAAUGAUCAUUAAAUGAUUACCUUAUCUAAGCAAAUGCUGAUUUAAGACAGAUAGCUAUAGGAUAUUUGUGAAGUAUCUAAUUAUCCUUGUGAUAAUUUUUCCUCACUACAUUUAUCCAGAAAAAGCCAGGAUUUUCAACUAAGUCUUUUAAAUAAGAAUCAAGGUUUUUAAAUUUCUGUGAAUCUUUACAAACAACUGGGACAAUUUUCUUUAAAAAUAGCUUCUUAAGGCAUGGAGCAGUGGCUCACGCCUGUAAUCCCUGUACUUUGGGAGACUUAGGCAGGCGGAUCAUGAGGUUAGGAGAUCGAGACCAUCCUGGCUAACACGGUGAAAUCCUAUCUCUACUAAAAAUACAAAAAAUUAGCUGGGCAUGGUGGCACAUGCCUGUAGUCCCAAGCUGCUUGGGAAGCUGAGGCAGGAGAAUCACUUGAACCAGGUAGGCGGAGGUUGCAGUAAGCCAAGAUGGCACCACUGCAUUCCAGCCUGGGCGGCAGAGCGAGACUCCAUCUCAAAAAAAAAAAAAAAAAAAAAAGUUGUUUAAAAAAUAAAUAAAAAUAAAAAUAGCUUCUUCCAAUUCCAUUUACAAUUAAAUUUUUUAUUCUCUUUAAUAGGUAACAUUAACAUAUCCUAGCAGCAAAAUACUAAAGAUAUUAUAAACAGGUAUUCAGUGAAGUCAUUCUCCUUCCAGCCCUGUCAGAGGCUCAAUCACUGAUACCAGUUUUUUAUAUAUUUUUCUAGAGACCUUUUUAGACAAAUACAAAGCUAGCUUCUCUUUUCUUUUUAUAUCAGAGGUGAUAUGCCACAUGCACUGUCCUGUGUGUUGUUUUUUUGUUUUGUUUUGUUUUUUACUUAGCAAUGUUAUCAUGGAACUGUGCCAAAUCUACAUUUUUUUUUUUAAUUUUUAGAGACAGGAUCUUGCUCUGUCAUCUUGGCUGGGAUGCAGUGAUGUGAUCAUAGCUUGCUGUAGUCUCGAACCUUGGGUCACAGAUGAUCCUCUAACCUCAGCCUCCUGAGUAGCUAGGACUAAAAGCAUGUGCCACCAUGCCCAGCUAAUUAAAAAAUAUAUAUAUGUGUGUGUGUAUAUAUAUAUUAUUUUUUUAACUGUGUUGGCCCAGGCUGGUCUCUAACUCCUGGCCUUAAGCAGUCCUCCCACCUUGGCCUCCCAAAGUGCUGGGAUUACAGGUGUGAGCCACCAUGACUGACCUGGUAUCAUUCUUUAACAACUGUAAAACAUUAGAUUGUGAUGAUAUUCUAUGACUUAACCAAUUACAUAUUUAGGUUGCUUCCAACCUUUUGCUUUUAUAAACAAGUUUGUGUGAAGAGCCUGGUACAAAUGUGUCUUUGAGUAUGCAUGCAAGUACAUCUGAAAGAUAAAUUCCUAAAUGUGGAAUUGCUGGGUCAAUAGGUAAGUGCAUGUAUAAUUUUGCUGAGUUGCUCUUGUGGAAGCCAAUAAUUCUACUCACAAUUCCACUGAUAAUGUGUGAGAGUACUUUUUUCCCCCAAGCAGAAAGUUUCUGUGGAUUUUUUUUGGGGGUGUUUCUGAGUUUUACUUAGAAAGGCCUUCCCCAUUUUGAGAUUAUUUUUAAAAUUCUUUGAUAUAUUUUAAUAUUUUCAUAAUUUCAUUUUUUAUAUUUAAACCUUAGGUACAGCUCAGAUAUAUUUUAAUACAAAGAAUAAGGCUAUCUUAAUUUUUUUUCUCAACUGGCUACCUAAUUGUCCCAAUAUCAUUUGUGAAUAAUCCAUCUCUCUCUCUUUCUCUCUAAUGGGAAAUGUCAGCUUUAUGAUUCCUAUAUUAAUUUGGGCUAUUCUUUAACUUUCUUGUAUCUGCCAGCGUAGGCUAGGUUAUGUUGUGGUAACAAACAACCUCAAAAUCUUAAUGGCUUAUAACAAGAAUUUUCCUUCCUUUUGGUACAUGUUCAUCAAGAGUUGGCUGAGAGCUCUACUCCGUGUCUUCUCACUCAGAAACUAAUGGAGUUGCCACCAUCUUGAACAUUACCAGCUUUCCUGACUAAGGGAAAGAGGGGCCUGGAGACUCUCACACCAUCAGUAAAAUGUUCAGCCUGAAAGAGAUAUACAUCAGUUCCCUUCACAGCUCGCUGACAAGUUUUAGUCACAUGACUCUACCCACAACAAAACAGCAGGAAAAUACAGUCAUACAUGUGUGCAGAAGGAAGAUGGAAAGCUGAAAAUAUUUGAACUUCCAGCACUAUGUUGAAUAAGAGUGGUGAGAGCAGAUAUCCUGCCUUGUUCCCGGUCUUAGGGGGUUCAUCCAUGAGCUCGGAUUUCCCACAUUACAACUUCAGGAUGCCUAAUAUUGGAUUCCAGAAUCUGCCUCUCAACAUAUAUAUUGUGGUUUUUGGUACUGCUAUAUUUGUCUUCAUCCUUAGUUUACUCUUCUGUUGCUACUUGAUUAGGCUAAGACAUCAAGCACACAAAGAAUUUUAUGCCUACAAACAGGUUAUAUUAAAAGAGAAAGUAAAAGAAUUGAAUUUACAUGAGCUCUGUGCAGUGUGCCUAGAAGACUUCAAGCCUCGAGAUGAGUUGGGGAUUUGCCCAUGUAAGCACGCCUUCCACAGAAAGUGCCUUAUUAAGUGGCUGGAGGUUCGUAAAGUGUGUCCCCUGUGCAACAUGCCAGUUCUACAGCUGGCCCAGUUGCACAGUAAGCAGGACCGUGGACCCCCUCAGGGGCCCCUUCCUGGGGCAGAGAACAUUGUAUAGCUUACCGCAAGGAUCAGACUGUUGCUGGACACGACGUCUGUGUGGAGCCAGGAGGAACACAUGUGGUGUCUGUAUGGCUGCUCUCUACCUAGGACACCAGCUGCCACUUCUUUUGCCUCAUGAAGAACUCUUGGGCCAGCCAAACUGGGAACCUAGGUGUCUGGGUCUUGUGACAACCAAAGCACUUUGACACUACCCCCUGCCGAGAGAAGAGGAGUGGAUGAGCCUGCGGGUUUGCCUCAAGAAACUUCAUGAGGGUCUCUUACUAACUCCAUUACACUCUCUCUCCUGGAGCCUCAUCUCCAUGUCAAGCAGGAGGGUAAAGAAGGGAACUAAGAGCAGGUCUUUCAAGCCACACCCCCACCUGCGGAUGGAUGGGUUUCUCUGUAGGCCAUGCAGGCCUUUGUCGCAGCAAACCUUCCCAGCAGCCCUUGAGCCAAGUAAAACCAGCACAACCAGCCACCAGUGGUUGGUGAGGCAGUGCCCACAAGGCUCAUGUUGUAUGCCUUUGAUAAGGCCAUCUUGGCUUUGAGUAGCAGUGUUCCUCGUCACCCAUUUCCCCCUCAGGAUUACAACACCUGCUAUCAAAUCAUCUAAGCUGAAAACAUGAGAUGCGCUUGGAAAGGCCUAGUCAGAAGCCAUUUCCUCUUAUCAUUUCCCUCUCCUAUGCACCAGUAAGGCCCGUCCAGAGCCCCAGCAGGGAGUGGGCCCUGAGUCCACACUGUCCCUGAGUGAUCCAGGAGGCUGCCCACAUCCCCACAUGUGCACUGUGGUUCCAGUGUAGCUGCUGUGAGCCCACUGCCACUGCCUCAGAAGGGAGCCACUGUGAACCUCUCGAGUGGCUCCAAAGAGCAGUGGCUUUUUGAGAAUGGCCCAUACUUCUGGCCCGGCUGGAUGAAGGGAAUGCCGACCCUUUGGCCUCUCCCCCUCCUUCCAUCUCUUCUCUCUCUUGCCCUAUCUCUCUUUCUACUUCAGAAAAAAAAAAAAAAAAAAAAAAAAGCCUGUCAUUCACUUUUUAACACUUUAUCCCAAAUAAGAUCCCUGUGUAAUUCUGAAGCUGGUGAUCCACUUGGAAUUGUAGAUAGUUUCAGGAAGCUCCUGCAGGGCUGUCCACCGUUGGUGUGUGCCUCAGUAUUUGGACUUCCGAAACUGAAAGUGAAAGUGUCUUUAUAGGAGAGAAACGCAUGCUGCUCUUUGGCUCUUUCUGUCCAACUUUUCUAGAAAUGACUCAAAGUCCAUUAAGAUUUGUGAAUAUUGUAUAAAUUAGCUAUGGAAAGUAGCAGGUCAGAUGGAAAAUUCUUUUCCACAGCCCUGCUCUCCGCCUCCCUCCAUCUUAGGAGCGCCUGCCUCAAUUCCUCGUCAACUGCUUUGCUCCACUCCAUCCCACAGGUGUGAGUGGGGGAAGUUUUUCAUUAGGAAUACAGUCUGCGUGACAUGGAGAAUGGAUGGAGGGAGCUUUGCUACUCUGCUCUUGGCAUGACUCCAGGAUUUUUUUCUGGAAUCCAACCUCUGUCCUCUUAGGAGAAGGAACCUGUCCUUGGUUCAGAUGGCUGGGCAUGAGGAGGAAAAUUUCCAUUAGUGUAGAACAGUGCUGGACAGAAUCCGGUUUGGAAAAUUACAAAUCCAGUUGGUCAAAAUAGGCCAUUUCCUAUGUGUGACCUAUUCGUGGUAUGCCAACUGGACUGCUUCCUAAACAGGACGAGGAAAGUGAGGAAUAUUUUUAUAUGAAAGCCUUAGCCUGUCUGGCACCCAUGAAAAAAACUAUUUAUGCACUCCUACUUUCACCGUCUUUUUGCAUUCUCUAUUUGUAGCACAACAGAGUUGAAUGCCACAAAACACCCCGUUUAUAGUGAGCUGUUUUCAGUGACCAAUAUCAGAAGGAGGCUUGCUUCUGGACUAGCCUCACUAAUUGCCAGCAGCCACCAUUUUCCAUGGAAUGGCCUUGGGACAGAUGUCACCUCUGUUAUGGGGCUCUAAUAGGAAAGAGAAUGUUUUUUCCCUUCCUAUGAUCAAUACUGCAAAUUAUUGCUGCUCACAGCUUUUAUAGGAUUCUCCCAACUGAAAGUUGCAGGCUUUUUCUGUCCCUGUGCAUCAGUACUAACAAAAGACAGCCUCACCAAGUCUGUAUAUUUGAACAGAGGCAAGUUAAUUCAUCCCCCCGUGUCAGAGCCACAGGCAUGUUGAGGGGGUUGAUACGUAGCACUGGACCAGGGCGCAAAGCCCAGAUAGUUCCAGCCAUGAGAGGAGAGCACAAGAAUGCUCUGCACUCUGCACUCAGCACCACCUUGGGUCUGCUUUGCCCAGAUGAGGGACCACUAACAACCUUCUCAGCACAUGUGAAUGUGGACUGGUUUUAAAAUGCAUUCAUUCUGCUAGGAUUGGGCUGGAAGCUGGAACAGUGAGAGUACUUUUUCUGCUCCUAGUCAUCUCCCUUUCUCAGCGUGACAUCCUCCUGCAGCAAGCCUAGUAUCACUAGCAGUAGUUCCUGCGACUCUUAGCAACACAACCCGAAUAUUUGCUCCCUGCAUCUGGGUCCUCCACCAGGAUGGGCCUGCGCAUCUGCAUUGCUGUACAGACAAACAGGCCUUUUAAUUUACAUCCUCCUUUAAUUCUCAUUAAAAUCGCAGGGUUUUUGUUUGAAAGACAGUCCUUUUUUUAUUUAUUUUGAAAAAGGAAUGAGUUAGGGACCCCUUUAUAACUCUCUUGGCUCAGACUCGAACCCCAUGGUAAAGUCACCCUUUCCGCAUCUAUCUUCAGGAGUUGCUGGGACUUGUUACUGUGUAGCUGCGUGGGGAUUCUGGUCUGCUCUUGGACCACUGGCUGGUAUCCUUUGUGUGUUUCUUAAGCAGCUCAAAGAUAGAAUGUUGCUGGUCUGCUAUGGGUUAGUGGAGCAUAACUCAGCCCCAACUGGACUCCACGGGUGGCUGAACCAUUAGUAGUUGCUAGGGGUACAACUGAAUUCAACUGCCUUCAGAAACAGGGAACAAAACCAGCCUGACUUGAUUCCUGGUUGGGUCAGUAUCAGACACUAGGAAGUUGACAUCUGCUGCUUUUCUUUGCCACGUGUGAUUUGGUUAGGCCUGUCCCUGGCAGAUAAGGUCCUUGAAGCCUAUGCUUGCCUAGCCAGGGAAGGCAGGACAGAAAUGGCCAAAUAGGGGCAGGUGGCCCCUGGGAAGGUCUGAGCUGAGGGAUACAGGGGACCUCCCACCAUUGCCGGAUACCCUGUUCUUGACAAGAAGAUCCUUUUCCCCAGUGCCAAGCCCCUUGGAUCCAUCAGAGAAAUAGCCUCGGGCCUUGUCCUUUUUCACAACCCCACUUCAAAAUCAUGUCAUCUCCCUGGCCUGAUCCCGCUCUAAGCUACUUUGAACAACUAGGAAUUAUUUUUCUCAGAGGCUUUUUGGGCAUUAUGAAAUACAUCCUGAUACAUCCAGGGCAGUAUACCCAGAGCUCCAGGCAGAGAGUGAUGGAAUCACCUCUUGUCACUCACUAGCCUUAGGCCCUUCUGCAGGUUAGCCUCUCAGUCUCUUCCUUAGCUUCCUUAGCUACCACCCAGGGAUUGUAGUAACGUCCCUGGCACCUCUUGUGGGGGUUAGCUGGUGCCCAGAGCCUGGUAGGCAGCAGGCCUGGUGUCAUGGGGGCUGCUGAUACCACAUAACAUCAUCUGGGUUACAUGGGCUCCUCUGCCAUCAUGAUUGAUAGGAACAGAACCUCAGCCAAAAAGCUUCCUGAGCUGUAGGGGCUUUCCCUGAGGCCCAGGUUCACCUGGCCCCUUUCUUCCUUGGUCAUCUCUGCCUUUGCCCACAGUGAACUCUGACUUGGUUGUUCAGUGCUGAAUAUUUCUUUCUUAAUGUUUUGAAUAGGUAAUCCAUUCAUGUGGUUCACAAAUCAUAAAGUAGUUAAAAGCCUUUCUUGAGUUCCUGAUGCCUAGCAAGCUCCGCUCCUCACUCCAUGAAUACCUACUAUUGGUUUGUUCCUUGGGUAUCCUUCCAGAGAUCAUUUAUGCAUGUACACACAUGUGUAUGUGUGUCUAUAUAAUUUUUCUCCUUUUCUACUCAUGUGAUACCAGACAAGUGUAUUCAAGGAACGCUCCUACUAAUGUGGGAAGAGCCAUCCCAGAAAUCAGAAUACAAAAUGUGAACCCAGAAUUGGGGGAUGUUUUUGCAAUCACACUCCUGUUGAGUAAGACAUAUUUUCAUUUUAUUGCAACAUACUGAAAUUUUAGUUUUCUGUACAAAUCAGAAUCUGCAGUCCCUCCCUUACCCCAAAUGCCCAGCUAAUCCAAGAGCACAACCAGAUUUUUCUGAUUGACUUUCUAUCUGCGACAGGAUGCUCAAGAUCAGGCUCUGUAGCUGACAGCAGUGGCACAGGCCUCUCCCAGCUCUGAGCAGCCUCUGCAGGUGCCUGGACAGCUGCUGGCCCCUCCCCUACCUUGGCCAGUUCCAAGUGAGGACCAGUGGUGAUGUGUGGCUGCAACUGUUGUGGUCACUUAGGCAAGCUCUUGUGUCUUUGAUGCAGGAGUUUGAGCAGCAGCAACUGAAGGCUUCUAUUUUGUGGGGCAGACAUCUUAGCUACUGAGCAAGUGCACAGUGAGUCUCAUGUGGAUAUGCCUGAAUGUCCAGCGUCAGUUCAUGGAGCUACUCCCUUUCCCUCCCAACUUUUCGUUGUUGUUGAGACAGGGUCUUGUUACCCAGACUGGAGUGCAGUGGCACCAUUGUAGCUCACUGCAGCCUCAACUUCCUGGACUCAAGUGAUCCUCCCGCCUCAGUCUGUAGCUGCGUCUACAGGUGCACACCAGCACACCUGGCUAAUUUUCGUAAUUAUUUUUUUGUAGAGACAGGUCUCAACUCACUAUGUUGCCCAGGCUGGCCUCCUCACUCUGUGCACACACUUUGAAAAGAAAAUGCUUCUGGUCGGGCGCGAUGGCUCACGCCUGUAAUCCCAACAUCCCAGCACUUUGGGAGGCCGAGGCAGGCGGAUCACCUUAGGUCAAGAGUUCAAGACCAGCCUGACCAAUAUGGUGAAACCCCCUCUACUAAAAAUACAAAAAUUUGCCGGGUGUGGUGACGCAUGCCUGUAAUCCCAGCCACUCAGGAGGCUGGGACAGGAGAAUUGAUUGAACCCGGGAGACAGAAGUUGCAGUGAGCCAAGAUCCCCACUGCACUCCAGCCUGGGCAACAGAGCGAGACUCCGUCUCAAAAAAACACACAAGAAAAGAAAAUGCUUCCUACAGAAUUUUCCCUUUAUGCCUUGUUUUCCAUUUGACAACAGAAAUUACCCCAACAAUUUUUUUUUUUUUUUUUUUUUUUUUUUUUUUUGAGACGGAGUCUCGCUCUGUCACCCAGGCUGGAAUGCAGUGGCACGAUCUUGGCCCACUGCAAGCUCCGCCUCCCAGGUUCACGCCAUUCUCCCGCCUCGGGAGCUGGGACAACAGGUGCCCGCCACCACGCUCGGCUAAUUUUUUGUAUUUUUAGUACAGACGGAGUUUCACCGUGUUAGCCAGGAUGGUCUCGAUCUCCUGACCUCGUGAUGCACCUGCCUUGACCUCCCAAAGUGCUGGGAUUACAGGCGUGAGCCACUGCGCCCGGCCAAUAAUUUUUUUAGUUUAAGUUCAUUUUUGUCCCCGCUGAUGAAAGUUAGAGCUGCUUCCUCCAGGCAGCCCUGGGAGUAGGGGCACAGACUUGUGCCUCGCUUCCCAGCAGCUGCCCAGUGCCUCUGUCCACACCCACCUCCCUGGUGUACUUGCCCCCUACAGCAGCAGCCCAGAUCCUCCCCUGGAUUAAAAUUGCAACUGGUGCCCUAACCCAAAACUUGAGAAAAAAUUCUCUAUCACAUCCACUCUUCUGGCAUUUGUAGAAUCUCUGGCCCUGGGUGUGUCUUUUCCUGUAGCUGUUACAGAUUUCUUAAGCAGAUUUCUUAAGCAGAUGGACAUGUCCAGAUUCAUGCCUAAAUAUCCAGUUGAUAACUGGAAAAUGCUGGUUCACGGUUCUUUAGUAAAGAUUAAUAAGGGAUCCCCAUGUGCUGGGGAGUGUGCUUCCAUUUGAGUGGGGAUAUCAGAAGAAAAAGAGGGGCUUGUGUAGUAAACCUUACUUUGCCAAUUCAGCUGUAGAGCCCAAAUUGUUACAAGAUGCAAAGAUGUACUCCACUUUUUGACCAAGCAUCAGCACCUUUGGCUUACCAUCCAGUCCUUACUUCUGUGACUGUAAGGGCCCCACCAGUGUCAGCAGACUUGUUUGUGCUUUGGGGGAACUCUCUUCUCAGCUCCCUUUGCCAGUCCCAAGCCUGGUGGAUCUGCAUCUCACGCCCACUGCACACCGUUCCUCUCCAUCUGCCCUUCCCUCCCAGGCCCCCGGUCGGGGGAGCAGGUGUGGCAAGUGUUAGGAACUCCCUUCUGGUGACAGCUGGUCUUCCUAGAGUGUUGCUGGUAACUAUCGCCUCUUGGUCUUCUGACAUCAUUGCCAGGAACGGGGCACUUUUUCGUCUUGUAGUUUGGCCCUCGGGUUUCCUCACUAGGUAUUGUGUAACUCCCUCAAAAAAAGGUUUAUGAAAUGCUGAACCUCAGGUUUCAUAGACGUCUUUGUACACUAAAAAUUCUGCAGCAGAAUAUUUUUAAACAUUCGCAGUUUUUUGUAAGCUAUAUUUUUGUAUAUUUAAUUGCUAUUUUAAAAUUUUAAUGCAUUUUGCUAAUCACUCCUCAAAAAUAAAACAUGCAUGUAAUUGACUCAAACGUGUAAAUAAAAGCAAAUUUUGAAAAA